AGUCGGGUGCCGAGAUUUGGGAGAGACGCUCUGAACUGACUGCCCCGCAUCACCGGAGCGUCCCAGCUGCGAGGAGGUAAGUGCCCUGACGUGACGGGGAGGGGCCGCAGCACUGCGUCUCAGCUUCCACUGCCGGUCUGGCCGCGGGCGGUUUUCCCCGGGCCCGCCCGCCUUGGGUCGCGUCGUCUCCCGACGCCUCCUGCCUGGGCCGGGCCUGGGCCUCUCCGCGCCCCCUUAUCUGCCGCGGCCUGUGCCUGCUGGAGCUCCGAGCUCCACGCUCUCUCCCCUUCCCGCCUUCCCGUCCUCCCGCGGUCCCCCGCCCCGUCUCGCUCCUCCGCCGUCUCCCGCCCAGCGGCAGCUUCCCCUUUUCGCCCUCCUUGGCCGCCCUUUGCCCCUUCCAGUCCUUUCUCUCUCGCCUCGGAGCCCCAUUCUCUUUGGCUACCUCUUCGGCCCCACUCCUUUCUUCUCCCGCAUCCCUUGUGCCUCGCUCCGACUCCAGCCUCUCGUUCUGACCCCAGGAAUCUCCCGAGGAGCGCAACUUCACAGCUGGAGACCCCGGGCGGGCAGUGCCCCUGGACAGCUCCCUGCUUGGCGUUGUCCCCACACUCCAAGCCCCGUCCUACCCCUCUGGGUUCUGACUAGGAAUUUUCCUCCGUUCAUGUUUAACCGCGACAGGCACAGACUCUGGGUGAAAAGAAAGAACUUUGUGCUUUGGCUGCAGCGCUGCGAGUAUAAAGGGAUGAGUGGGUUGCACGGAGAGGUGUGAAUGUGCUUUUUGUCCUGGGGGCCGAUUGUUUCCUCCCGGUCUAGUUUGCCUCUUAGAGUUGCUGGGUUUGGUUUUCUUCCCCAUACUCUACGCUUUCUGGUGGUCUGGGAGUUUCGAAAUCUUUAAUGUUGUGAUGACAACGCUUACCCGCGCAUCCCUUCUUGAUCGUUCUUAGGUCUUCUCAGGGGCCUGGAAGUGUAGACCUAGGCUUGGGAUUCAAGGAGGUCUUGGUUAAAACGGCAAGAUGUAAAUAAGAUUGUGACGCAUCCAUUUUGUUGAAAGAAAAAACCAGGAAUUUGGCCUUUUGAUGGAGGAACUUAGAAGAACUUUGUAAUUUUUGUAAGGUUGUGGAAAAUCCGAGGCAAAGUUAAAUUGCCUGGUGUGAUUUGACUUUAACUUCGAAUAGGCUUUUUAAAGUUUCAUCUCUUUGGAGAUUGUUCAACUUCACGAGUUCACUGCAGUGAAAACGCCAAGACUGUCUCCCACAAAUUUAAUAUUAAUGAAGAAAGGCAAGCCAAUUAUAUCUGUUGUCCGGAGUUAGUUGUACAGCCCUUUCUUUGAAUGGGGAUCUGGGGAUGCAGAGGAGCAUAAUGAGCCUUUUAUAAUUACAAACAUGCUCUUCUCUAGCUCUUAAGGUUAUGCCUAACGCUCAUUUGCUCUUGGCUAAAAUAACUGAGAAAAAAAGUGAGUAGUAAAAAAAUGCUGGAAGUCUGAAAAUGGUUUAGACAGAACUUCAUUCCUGAAGUUUUAGUCUGUAGCCAGAUUUUAAUUCUGGCCUGUUUUGGUUUUUAGAUGAUAGAUCUUUUAGUGUGUCAACAGGAAUGUAAAGUUUGUAUUAACAUCUAGGGUGAUCACCUGCCAUGCUAUUAAGUCAGCAUGGUAUAAUUAAAAGUUACAUAUGUAGGUUCAGAGCCUCUUAGCACAGUGUUACAUUGUAAGCUCUUGGAGGGCAGGAAUGAGAUUCUAGUCCUUACGGAAAUGGAGUUUGGGCUUCUAUCCCUAGCAUUCAUUCUAGUGCCAUGCACGUGGUAGGAAUUCUGUAAAUAUUUGUGAAAGAAAUGAAUUUCUGCCUGUAGGGUUCAGCAGUGUAUACUUAAAUGUGAUGUGUACGUAAAUGCUGACUGAUUUCCAGAGAGGGCUAAAGAGGACUUGGGGGGCGGUCUGCGGGUUGGGGAGAUUGGCUCAGAUGAUUUAUGAACUCGGUAAGAGCUGAACAUUGACUAACGGAUCAUAAGGUAAUUGAGGAACAUUGUAAGUCAAACUUCAAUUUAGUUCUACCAGCAGGAAGGAUUUGUUUACAACCUGCAAUAGUACUCUUUUAGAUGAUGUGAAGCUUUGAAAAUAUUGAAAUAAGUGAUUGCUCACCUCUCCCCCCAGGUAUAUAGGAAUUGAUUGUGUAUUUGGGGGAUCCUACCCUAAACUGAGAAUUAGAGACUAGUGAAGCAUGGGAUUGUGUGGAUAAUGUUUCUUCAUGUUUAUGUACUUAAAUAAACCAGCAAAAUAUACGUCGAGAAUGUAUCUAAAUUAUUUUUUUGUCCUAAGAAGUUGAGGUGCAGGCUGGCUGAAUUUUUUUUUUUUUUUUUAGUAGCUGAAUUCUUUUGAGACUGUUUUCAGUGUUCCCCAGAGAGCUCUGCCUAAAAUACCUUAACUUCCGCAAAUAAGUAAAGUGAAAAGUCCUGAUUCCUUGCCUCUUUAUUUUGCGCUGGUACUACAAUAAUAUAAUGGUUACUUUAUAUCAAACAUUAUGACACCUUGACCUUUGGAAUAUUAGAGGUCUCACAAUAACUUCGGAGCCACCUUGAGAAACGAGCAGAUAUGAAUCAGAGAGGACCCAAGGGCCGUUGGAGAGGCACUGCUCCCUCUGAGAAUGCCCAAGAGGGGUGGGGGCGGGGGGGGGCGGGUAAAGGCUUAGAAAUAAAGAGGUGAAGUGAACCUUUUGCUUCAAAUAUUCUCUAUUUCUAUUUUUUUUGUGGUACUUUUCUUCUGAUUCUCUCUGAUAUGUUCAUAGAUGCUGGUUUGCUUAAUUUGUAUUCAAAAUUUGGUACUAAUAACCCUGAGUGAAAAAAUAAUUUGGAGACUAGAUUCAAGGGUUUAUUAACAGACUUCUCUGUUGUGUUUCUUGUUGCUUUGGUUGGUUCUUCAUCUACCUUUCUCUGUUUAAAUAUAAAAAUCAGGUGGAAAAUAUGGAGGACUUUGAUUAAUCAAACUAGUUAAGAGAUCAUUUAGUGGUGCGUCUACACAAUAGUCAUUUCUGUUUUUUUUCUUUACUUUCAACCUUUCUUUAGGCUAAAGAGAAGUUUGUUUGUUUUCUUUUCUUUUUCCACUCAUGUGCACAAUGAAGUUUUUAGGGGGUUGCAAGUGUAUAGUUCAUUUAUUUUCUUUCUUGUUUAACAAUUAAUUACACUAUUCCAGGCUAUGAAGAAAAACACAAAUGGAAGUAUCAACCUUACUGGUAGAGUGCAUUUCUAAUUCUGCUUUCACAGUGGUAACGUCUUGUUCUCUAAAACGUGUCUUCCUGUGAACAUAGCUGUCUGGGUCAGGACUGCUCUAGAGAAAUGCUAUCAUGUGUCAUGAAAGUUAUACUUAACUAGGGUUAGGCCAGACAAAUACUCAGUGUCAUUUUAAAGAAUCAGAGUGCUAUAAUUUUAGCUAUUCCCUUUUAUUUCUGAUGUCAUUUUGUUCAUAGGUUUCUAGACCAACUGGGGAGAUUCCCGUUAAAAAUGUAAACAGGAACAUCGAUAAGUAGUGUAAAAACUUGCACAAUGAAAUCCGAAGCCAAGGAUGGAGAGGAGGAGAGUCUACAGACUGCUUUCAAAAAAUUAAGAGUGGAUGCAUCAGGGUCUGUAGCAUCUCUGUCUGUUGGAGAAGGCACAGGUGUCAGAGCACCAGUCAGAACAGCAACAGAUGAUACCAAACCUAAAACCACAUGUGCAUCUAAAGACAGUUGGCACGGGUCUACAAGGAAGUCUUCACGAGGAGCAGUGAGAACUCAGCGUCGUCGACGUUCUAAGUCUCCUGUCCUUCAUCCUCCAAAGUUUAUACAUUGCAGUACAAUAGCGUCUUCUUCCAGCAGUCAACUCAAGCACAAAAGCCAGACUGACUCACCUGAUGGCAGCAGUGGGCUGGGAAUUUCAUCCCCUAAAGAGUUCAGUGCAGGAGAAAGCUCUACUUCUCUCGAUGCUAAUCACACAGGGGCAGUCGUUGAGCCUUUGAGAACUUCUGUUCCAAGGCUCCCAUCAGAGAGUAAGAAGGAAGACUCCUCUGACGCUACCCAAGUCCCCCAAGCAAGUCUCAAAGCCAGUGAUCUCUCUGACUUUCAAUCAGUUUCCAAGCUAAACCAGGGCAAGCCAUGCACAUGCAUAGGCAAGGAAUGCCAGUGUAAGAGAUGGCAUGAUAUGGAAGUGUAUUCCUUUUCAGGCCUGCAGAGUGUCCCUCCCUUGGCUCCAGAACGAAGAUCCACACUUGAGGACUACUCUCAGUCGCUGCACGCCAGAACUCUGUCUGGCUCUCCCCGAUCCUGUUCUGAGCAAGCUCGAGUCUUCGUGGAUGAUGUGACCAUUGAGGACCUGUCAGGCUACAUGGAGUAUUACUUGUAUAUUCCCAAGAAAAUGUCCCACAUGGCAGAAAUGAUGUACACCUGAUAGCAAGAAGCUAAUUCAUAUGCUUUAAACCAAUGAAGGCUUGUCAAAGAGAUUUAGUUAAUGGCAGACCUUGUGGCCACUUUGUGUGAGAAGACAUCUCUUUCUGCUCACUGUGCUUGCAAUAAAAACUUUUCUUGGCAUCUCAGUUAAUCUUCAUUCUUUCAACUUACUCUCUUGAGUUCUUACAUACACUUCAAGGCGAGCAGAUCAAAGAAAAAUCCCCCUUAUUUAGAAAUGUUCCUGGGGGAUGAAGAAACCAUAAUUACUUGAGACUGGCAGCAGUGGGUAUAUGGUAAAAGCCUUUGUAAAACAGUGCAUUUUUCAGAUUUGUUUAAGGUUUGCUAGCCAAGGAAAGUAAAAUGUGAUUUUGUAACUGCACUAAACAUUUGUCAUGCUGUAGUUGCCAGCCCAGAAUAUUAGAAGUUACAAGACUGAUUUAAACCGUCUCUGAUUUAAUGCAAGAUAUAUUGUGUCUAUAAAGGUUUCUCUUGUUAUUGUUAAGCCAGAGAUCUAAGGUUUAGAUUCAAUUUGAAUAAACUAGCUGGCCUGCCCUCUAUUGUUUGAGAGAGUUAUUAACCAUCACUAAAUAAGCCCCUGCUGGUGCUAUUCAUCCUAAGACAUGUUACAUGCAGUUUCAAGUAAGCAGCUUGGAAUGGGCUGCUUCAGUUGGAGGGAGGGGGUGUAAUAUUUGAAACGAGUGUGUGUCUUCACCAUCUCCAGCAUUUUAAAUAUAUGGCGGUUUUUUUUUUUUUUUUUUGUUAUCAGUUGUAAUACAGGUCUCAUACCUCAGUUUCAGAUGUUAUAGAUGGUUACCUCUUUGAGCUGCCCUGUCACCCCAGCAACCCUAAAAGAGAAUUUUGUACAUUCUGUAUCCCACAGAUUUGGUCAGCCAUUUCAAAAUUCCCUCCAGUUUGGUAAAAAAAAAAUCUGUCUUCGGUUUCAGCUGGAUGAUGAAUCCUUGUUUUUCAGGUGGCUCCAAAAAGAAUGUUGCAUGUGUUCAGACCAUCCUGAGCAGAGCCACCAAAUUUAGUGACAGUGUCUAGCCAUGUUAGCAAUAAUGUUAACAGAAGCUUUUGUUUAAAUUACAAAAUACAUUUAUACUAUUUACUAAAA